ACUCUUCCUGUUGGAGUCCUGAUCGGAGGAGUGCGGGCCGGAGGGUGAUGGGACCAUCUAGCCCCUAACCAUGGGCCCAGAAGAGAAGACCAUCAUGACAGAAAGGUCUGCAGCUGUUUUCAUCCAGGCCUGGUGGCGGGGCAUGCUGGUGCGACGCACACUGCUGCAUGCAGCCCUCAGGGCUUGGAUCAUUCAGUGCUGGUGGAGGCAGGUGCUGGAGAAGCUGCUGGCAAAGAGGCGGAGGAUGGUGUUGGAGUUCUAUGUGCAGCAGGAAUGGGCAGCAGUCAGGCUGCAGUCCUGGGUCCGCAUGUGGUGUGUCCGCCAGCGUUACUGUCGUUUGCUCAACGCUGUCCGCAUCAUCCAGGUCUAUUGGCGCUGGCACAGCUGCCAUUCCCGUGUCUUUAUUGAGGGCCACUAUGAACUCAAAGAAAACCAACUUAAUAUUCAACUUGAAAUCUCUUUGGGCUUACAGGCUUGUAAGGUGCAACAAUGCAUACCCCUUCCAUUAAAAGAAUGACCAGGUCUGCUA